GAGUCCAGGCUGCCCGCGCCGGCGGCCGCCCGCCCCUCGGACACUGCCCCCGCCGCCGCCGGAGCUCUGCAGCACGGUAAGGCUGAGGGCGGGUGCAGGAAGUCUGACUGUUCUGGGGGUUCCGGGGUACACUUGUAGCCCCCAGUUAUGGUCCCCAUCGCUGAGGAUCGGGGUCCCAGGGGUGCUUCGAGUCGGUAGACCCUAAAGUUUGCUCUGAGCACACGGCCCACCUGGCGCUGCGGGCGGCCACCCCCUUCUCGAACCAGCCCGGCUGGGCUGGGCGCAGCUCGAAACGCCGGAGACCACGGCCUUUGGCUCGGCGCCCGUCGGGCGUCUGAAAUCCGGCGGGGACAGCCACGUACCGGGGAGGAAAGGUAGAAGGGCGCAAGCUCCUCGGGCUACGCUGGGCUACUGGGAGGCUCCCACUCUGUCCCAGCACCCCCGGGUCGCUUGCAGCCUGGGUGUCACCGGCGACGGUGCCUUCACAUGCCAGCUGCCUGAGCCCAGGCCAGUAGGCAGUGGGCGCUGGAUGAAGGAUUUCCCCACCCCAACGCUGUUUGCCGCCUCUGAGCGAGAGUGUGGAGUGUGCGCGCCGAAUCCGCUGCCCUGCACUCCCUCCCCUGCCAACUCCUGGGAAGCGCAGCCCGGAGCUGAGCUGGUGUUCAGGGCAGCCCGGACUGGGUUCCUGCGGAGCAGCCCCGGCGCCCCUGCGUCAGAGUCCGCGCUUCAGGUUCCCCAGCAUCCGCGCGACGACAGAGCUGGGCGCCCGGCGCCGGCUAGCGCGGGCGGGAAGCCCCCCGGAGCGCCGCCAAAUACUUUUCUCGGCCAGUUGGCUUGGCCAGGCUCCGUCCCAAUGCAGUGUGUCCGAAGCCUCCUGGAAAGCUGGAGAUGUCGUCUGAUUCUGAUCCGUGAUUAAAUUCGGACUGAGCAGACACUAAUAGGAUUAGCCUGCCAGAAAGCUCGGCCCUGAAGCCAUCGGAACCUGUGCAAACACGCGCCUCGGGCUGGAGCAUUCACUCCCGCCCCGCCGCGCUUCUGCAGCUGGGUGCGGCUGACCUGGGCACCCGGAGUGUGGCCCUGUGUCUAGGUCGUUUGGGAAACGCCUUGGAGAGUCAAGAAUAAAUUUGCAGGUCAAACAAUGGAUGACUGGAAAAGUCGGCUUGUAAUCAAGAGCAUGCUUCCCCAUUUCGCCAUGGUGGGAAAUCGUCAGGAGCCCAGAAAGCUCCAGGAAUCGGGAAAGAAGCCCUCGUGGAUGGAGGAAGAAGAUUUAUCUUUUCUCUACAAGAGCAGCCCAGGAAGAAAGCAUCAGGGAACUGUUAAGAGGAGACAAGAAGAAGACCACUUCCAGUUUCCAGACAUGGCUGAUGGGGGCUACCCUAAUAAAAUUAAGAGGCCUUGCCUUGAAGAUGUCACCCUUGCAAUGGGCCCAGGUGCUCAUCCUAGUACUGCUUGUGCAGAACUGCAGGUCCCUCCAUUGACAAUAAAUCCUAGCCCUGCGGCUAUGGGAGUGGCUGGCCAGUCAUUACUGCUGGAGAAUAACCCUAUGAAUGGCAACAUCAUGGGCUCACCAUUUGUAGUACCACAGACUACAGAAGUGGGACUGAAAGGGCCCACUGUUCCUUACUAUGAGAAAAUCAACAGCGUGCCGGCUGUAGACCAGGAGCUUCAAGAGCUGCUAGAGGAGCUCACCAAAAUUCAAGACCCUUCUCCAAAUGAGCUAGAUCUUGAGAAGAUACUGGGGACGAAGCCAGAAGAGCCACUGGUUUUAGAUCAUCCCCAGGCAACCCUAAGCACAACUCCCAAGCCUUCGGUUCAGAUGUCACACUUGGAGAGCCUGGCUUCCAGCAAGGAGUUUGCUUCUAGUUGCAGCCAAGUUACUGGCAUGUCACUUCAGAUCCCAUCCUCCUCCACAGGGAUCAGCUAUUCGAUUCCUUCCACCAGUAAGCAGAUAGUGUCACCGAGUUCUUCAAUGGCACAGUCCAAGAGCCAGGUCCAGGCCAUGCUCCCUGUCGCUCUGCCCCCCUUACCAGUGCCUCAGUGGCAUCACGCCCACCAGCUGAAGGCGUUGGCAGCCAGCAAGCAGGGGUCUGCUACAAAGCAGCAAGGGCCCACCCCCAGUUGGUCUGGUCUGCCUCCUCCAGGACUCUCUCCACCUUACCGCCCAGUGCCAUCACCACACCCACCACCGCUGCCACUGCCACCACCACCACCCCCAUUCAGCCCCCAGAGCCUCAUGGUGUCCUGCAUGUCGUCCAAUACCUUGUCGGGUAGCACUCUCCGAGGCUCUCCCAAUGCCUUACUGUCAAGCAUGACGUCCAGCAGCAAUGCUGCCCUGGGGCCCGCCAUGCCCUAUGCUCCUGAGAAGCUCCCCAGCCCUGCUCUCACUCAACAGCCGCAGUUCGGCCCUCAGAGCUCCAUUCUUGCCAACCUCAUGUCCUCUACCAUCAAAACCCCUCAAGGACACCUGAUGUCUGCUCUGCCUGCCAGCAACCCUGGGCCGUCCCCACCCUAUCGCCCAGAGAAGCUCUCUAGCCCAGGCUUGCCACAGCAGUCCUUCACCCCACAGUGUUCCCUGAUCCGAAGCCUCACUCCCACCAGUAAUCUUCUAAGCCAGCAACAGCAGCAGCAGCAGCAGCAGCAGCAAGCAAAUGUGAUCUUUAAGCCCAUAAGCAGCAACUCAUCCAAAACCCUGAGCAUGAUCAUGCAGCAGGGGAUGGCAAGCUCCAGCCCAGGAGCCACGGAGCCAUUUACUUUUGGCAACACCAAGCCCUUGUCCCAUUUUGUUUCUGAGCCGGGUCCCCAGAAGAUGCCCUCCAUGCCUACCACCUCUAGGCAGCCUUCCCUGCUCCACUACCUGCAGCAGCCGACACCAACGCAGGCCUCCUCAGCCACUGCCUCCUCCACGGCCACUGCCACCUUGCAGCUGCAGCAGCAGCAGCAGCAACAGCAGCAGCAGCCUGACCAUUCUUCAUUCCUUCUGCAGCAGAUGAUGCAGCAACCCCAGCGUUUUCAGCGAUCAGUGGCCUCAGAUUCCAUGCCUGCUCUGCCCAGACAGCAAGAGGAACAGAGAUCAGGUCUUAUGGCAAUGACCCCUGAACGGCAGAAUGCAUAUAUCUCCCAACAGAUGAGUCCAUUUGAAGCCGUCCAAGAACAAGUCACCUCCAAGUGUAGCCGGAUCAAGGCAAGCCCCCCAUCUAGCAAGCACUUGAUGCCACCCAGAACUGGGCUUCUUCAGAACAAUCUGAGUCCAGGAAUGAUCCCACUCACCAGGCACCAGAGCUGCGAGGGCAUGGGAGUGAUCUCACCAACUCUGGGGAAGCGGCAAGGAAUUUUCACCUCCAGCCCCCAGUGUCCCAUCCUCUCACACUCAGGCCAGACUCCCCUGGGCAGACUUGACUCUGUCUGCCAGCAUAUGCAGAGUCCCAAGGCCACCCCACCAGAAGUGCCCCUGCCUGGGUUCUGUCCCAGCUCCCUGGGCACCCAGUCCUUGAGUCCCCACCAGCUCAGACGGCCUAGUGUGCCAAGAAUGCCCACUGCGUUCAACAAUGCUGCAUGGGUCACAGCGGCAGCAGCUGUGACCACAGCAGUUUCGGGGAAAACACCCCUCAGCCAAGUGGAUAAUAGCGUUCAGCAGCACUCACCUUCUGGCCAGGCCUGCCUUCAGAGGCCAUCUGAUUGGGAGGCACAAGUGCCCGCUGCGAUGGGAACACAAGUGCCCCUGGCCAACAACCCCAGCUUCAGCCUGCUGGGCAGCCAGAGCCUCAGGCAGAGCCCGGUACAGGGCCCGGUGCCUGUAGCAAACACCACCAAGUUCCUCCAGCAGGGUAUGGCCAGCUUUAGUCCCCUGAGCCCCAUACAGGGCAUCGAGCCACCAAGCUAUGUGGCUGCUGCUGCCACCGCUGCUGCUGCUUCUGCCGUUGCUGCCAGCCAGUUCCCAGGUCCGUUCGACAGAACGGAUAUUCCCCCUGAGCUGCCACCUGCCGACUUUUUGCGCCAGCCCCAACCCCCACUAAAUGAUCUGAUUUCGUCACCUGACUGCAAUGAGGUAGAUUUCAUUGAAGCUCUCUUGAAAGGCUCCUGUGUGAGCCCAGAUGAAGACUGGGUGUGCAACUUGAGGCUGAUCGACGACAUUUUGGAACAGCAUGCUGCUGCUCAAAAUGCCACAGCCCAGAAUUCUGGGCAAGUCACCCAGGAUGCUGGGGCACUUUAAAUCUGAGCAGGAUGCCCAUAGAAACCCCCAUGGUGACAUCACUCUAGGAAGUGGUGUCGAUCCAUACCCGCAGUUGUCUCCCGUUACAAUUUGAGUGGUGUUGUCAGCCCAUGCUUAUCCCUCUCUCUACCUGUGACAAAAUGGAAAGCUGGUGAUUUUUCAAGCUACGUGUACAUAUUUGAAAAUUUUGUAAAUGGUUUUCCUAAACAUUAAUGACAGAAGUAUUUAUACUUCAUUUUGUGACUUUGUAAAUAAAGCGACGGCUUUUGUUUCAGUAGAGUUGUGUUUACUAUGCAUUGUUUUGUGUUUAUUAUACAAUGUUACAAAUAUGCAGACCGUGUUGUUUGCUCCAGUGAUACCUUGUUAAGCUAGGUGGCUGAGUCGCUUAUGGUUUUAAUGCAAUGAGCAAUGUGGAUAUGACCAAGAGUUGUUGUGCAAGUUGACAAAUGCCAAAUAGAAAACCACUUGGCCAUUUAUUUCUAUGUUCACUAAAAAUCCUAUUGCCUUGUGUGAUUCUUAAUCUCUUUUGCGAACCUUUCAGUCUCCGCUAGCUCUUUCCUAAUGAGCUUUACAGCAGAAGCCGUUUUAUCGUUAAGUGCCCCACAGAGACACUUUACCAGGAGGCUGGGAGAGUUCUCCAGAUUUGGGAGAGGCGCAGAGACAGUGUGUGAGCCGAGCCCUGUCUCAGCAAUCCACCUGGAGGAGCUAGAGUAUCCUCCUCCCUUUACCAUUCAGACCGAGAGAAAAAGCCCAGCUUGUGUGCACCCUCGUGGGGUUAAGGCGAGCUGUUCCUGGUUUAAAGCCUUUCAGUAUUUGUUUUGAUGUAAGGCUCUGUGGUUUGGGGGGGAACAUCUGUAAACAUUAUUAGUUGAUUUGGGGUUUGUCUUUGAUGGUUUCUAUCUGCAAUUAUCGUCAUGUAUAUUUAAGUGUCUGUUAUAGAAAACCCACACCCACUGUCCUGUAAACUUUUCUCAGUGUCCAGACUUUCUGUAAUCACAUUUUAAUUGCCACCUCGUAUUUCACCUCUACAUUUGAAAUCUGGCGUCUGUUUCAAGCCAGUGUGUUUUUUCUUCGUUCUGUAAUAAACAGCCAGGAGAAAA